CUUGUGAUCCGCCUGCCUCGGCCUCCCAGAGUGCUGGGAUUACAGGCAUGAGCCACUGCGCCUGGCGCUUUUCACAUUUCUUAUGCUAACUUGAUAUAUUUCUGACGUGAGAAAAAAUUUUAAAUGGUCCAUUUUCAAGGCAUGAUAAAUCUAAGUACUGGCAGCCAGCCUGCAAAUGUAACAAACCACAUGGCUCAUGCACCAAAAGGCCACGAUAAGUGAACAGAAUGUAGAGGAGGGGUCAGCCCAUAAAAGGGAAGAAAGUUUUGUUAUUGGGAAAUCAAAAGUUAAGUGGGGAAGGGGACGGGUUAUAACCUUAUAAGGGGGAUAAUGAAACUCAGGCGAUGUCUGGGAAGAUUGUAACCCCAUAGUACUCCGCCAGUGAGGAACUGGGGAAGGGACUUGUGUGCUAGGAGAUAAAUUAUCUCUUGUGACUGCCCCAGGUGUGCCUGCCCACCGGACGCCCAAUCUUGCAAGACCAUUAUUAAAAGUCUCACUUUCGCUGUUCUUUGUCCCUCUAAGUCCAUUCUUUGGGUUUGGACAGGUGAGCAUGUCUCUCACAACCUGGGGACCCAUCCGGGGUCUCUAUGCCUGCAUGGAGUGGUAUUCCGGCCAAGAGAGGAGAUACAUCCCACCUGAUUUAGGUGGCCCACUCUGUCCAGGCGUCCUGGCUCCCCACAGAAGCCAUAGAGAAAUCUGAGACUGUUAUUCAGGAGGCAGCAGAGGUGACCCAGGGAGAAAAGCAGGCACCGUGGGAACCAGCCCACCUCAUGCAUGAGCCAAGGUAGGAAAAUUGGACUAUGAGUAGAGUACUGCCUUGGUGGUUGGGCCUUUUCGAAGGUUCUGGGGUGUGCAAGAAACCUCCAGUAAGGGGGGCUGAGUAAACAGGGAAAAACUCAGACACAGAGGCUGGCCGAAAAUGGGAGACAGAAAUUCUAGGCCUAGGGGACAAAGGGAAGAGGGAGCCAAAGAGACUCCCUCUGACAUUCCCCCAGAUAGUCCUUUGGGGAAAAUGUUGCAGGUUUGGAGGAACAACCCUUGAACCAGAGACAAGGAAAAGCAAAACAUUUAGAGUAUUGCUGUUUUAUCUGGCCCAAAGACCUGAUUUGUAAGCCUUUGGUCUUUUGGCCUAAGUUUGGCUCAGAUGAGGAUUGGGUGUGCCAAGCUUUAAUUCUCUAUGUGAAUUAGAGAGAUAGGUUACACUCUCUGCUGGAUUAAGGAAUUAGCCCCCUUGUUCCCCCUCAAAGAAGAAAGCCUAGUGAAAAGCCCUGGGACCCCCUAUCAUGCUCACCCCUCCAUAAGCCUCUCAAGAUAGGGGACAGGAAGAUCAAGGGGCAGCAGGAGGGUUAGAGGAAGAAAGACCCGGAGACCAUGGGGAAGCCAAACCAACUGCUCCUUUAAAUCCUUAUCCAAAUUAAAGAAAAGAAUUAAAACAGUGUAAGAGAGAGAUCGAAAACUUACCUAUCCCUUCCACACAGCAGGCAUCUAGCAUGUUCACGCUUACGCAAGUUCCCAUGGGACAAGGAAAAAUUGGCUUUGUAAAUGCUCCUCUUACAAGAACUGAAGUUAGGAAUUUCAAGAAGCAAAUGAAACCACUCCUACAAGAUCCCAGCCAUUUAGCAGACCAAUUCCUGGAACCCAGCUUUUAUACCUGGGCUGAAAUGAUGUCUGUCAUGAAUAUCCUGUUCACAGGAGAAGCGGGGAAUGAUUAGGAGAGCUGUUCUUCAUGCCUCUAAGUCCAUUCUUUGGGUUUGGACGGCUGAGCAUGUUUCUCACACUGAGCGCCUAGUUUCUCAACUUAGUAGGAAUGAGAAUGAUUUAAACUGUUUGUAAACAGAUUUUCAGGUCACUCCAGAAAUUUGAUCUUUAGGGGAGGGGCCUGGAAUUUUUUUAACAGGUGCCCCAAAAGUAAUUCUCAAUCAAGUUUGGUGAACAUUCCCUUAGUCAAUAGAGUUAACUUGCUAGGCCUCCUAGAAACAACUAGAAAUGCUGUCCUGAGCAUUACAAAGUGCCAAAAGAAACAAUAAUUUGAGAGUUUUAGUACAGGUUCCGAUUUUAUUAUAGAACAUAUGGGAGGAGUAAAAUGGGGGAGGAUAUAUUUUGAGGGAAGAGUACCUUCUAAACUUUUAACCAGCAUCCCUAAAUAUAUGAACGUUUACGAAUUAUCUGCCUGUCCUAAUGUUGUGUAUGGUUUUGGCUUUUUGUUGUUGUUGUUGUCGUUUUUGUUUUGUUUGUUUUGUUUUGAGAUGGAGUCUCGCUCUGUUGCCCAGGCUGGAGUGCAGUGGCGUGAUCUCGGCUCACUGAAAGCUCCGCUUCCCGGGUUCAAACCAUUCUCCUGCCUCAGCCUCCCGAGUAGCUGGGACUACAGGCGCCCGCCACCACGCCCGUCUAAUUUUUUGUAUUUUUAGUAGAGACGGGGUUUCACUGUGUUAGCCAGGAUGGUCUUUAUCUCCAGACCUCGUGAUCCGCCCGCCUCGGCACCCCAAAGUGCUGGGAUUACAGGUGUGAGCCACUGCACCCGGCCCCUGUUUUUUUGUUUUUUUUUGUUUUUGAGACAGAGUCUGGCUCUUUCGCCCAGGCUGGAAUGAAGUGGCAGGAUGUUAGCUCACUGCAACCUUUGCCCCUGGGGUUCAAGUGAUUCUCCUGCCUCAGCCUCCCGAGUAGCUGGGAUUACAGGCGUCUGCCACCAUGCCCGGUUAUUUUUUGUAUUUUUAGUAGAGAUGGGGUUUCACCAUGUUGUCCAGACUGGUCUCAAACUCCUGACCUCAGGUGAUCCACCUGCCUCGGCUCCCAAAGCAUUGUGUAUGUUAUUAAAUAUACCCAAAGAAGUACAUUUUUAAGGAUGAAAAUACUUAACUAGAAACUUUAAUAUUUCUUUGGAUACCUAGGGGAUUACUUUGAAUGAGACCACAUCAAUUUGGAAUCCACUGAAUAUACAGCAUGGAAACCUCGUGGGCCUUCCUCACUAGUUUUUCUCUUUUUCAUUUUUUCUGGAAAAGGGGGUGAAGAUGAAGAAGGAAGUGAAAAAAGAUUGUGUGAAAAAAAAUGUGCGUGUGUGUAUGUAUAUAUACAUAUAUAUGUUAACAUAUGUAUGUUAAUUGCUGCAUAACAAAAGACUACAAUUUUAACUGCUUAGAACAACACCCAUUUAUUUGCUCCGUAGGUCAGAAUUCUAGGCAUAGCCCUAGUGUGUUUGUUCUCUGCUCAGAGUCUCACAAUGAGCAAUGAAUUUGACCAGGUUGCUGUCCCAUCUGAGGCUCAUUCCGUUUGUUGUCAGAAUUCACUUUUAUGUGGUCCUAGGGCUGAGGUCCCUGUUUUCUGGCUGUCAACCGGGGACUCUUGAACUCUGGUGCCAUGCCCUACCACAUAGCCUUUUGACAUCAUGGCAGUUUGCUCCUUCAAAACCAGCAAGAGAGUUUCACAUUUGAAUCUCUUUGACUUCCUCUGUCACUGACCUUUAGACCCAGAUUUAGAGGGCUCAAGUGAAUAUCUUAGGUCCACUGACAUAAUUUCCCUUUGAGUUGAUUAACUCAAAGUCAACCUUAAUUAUAUCUGCAAAAUCAUUUGUAUUAUGUAAGGUAAACAAUCAUAUUCACAGAAUUUCAUCCACAGUCAAGAGGAGGGGAUUAUACAAGGUAUACACCAGAGGGUGAAAACCUUGGGGACCAUUUUAGAAGUCCGCAUGCUACACGUGACAUGGAACUAAAGUCUUUUUUCAUAAUUGCUAUACUUAAUAUUCCAUAGUUUUAACUCAAGGAGCUGAUGAAUUAAACAUAAAAUGUUUCAGUGAGAGAAAAGUCCCUUGAUGAAUUUUAAACAGCUUUUAAAGAAGUCUCCCACCCCUAGGUUGCUAGGUUGCUUUGUGUGUGUGUGUGUGUGUGUGUGUGUGUGUGUGUGUGUGUGUGUGUGAGAGAGAGAGAGAGAGAGAGAUUUUGAUUCGUCUAGAAAUGGAUUUGCUCUGCUUGUUUUGAACAGUCAGAAUUUGGAUAUAGCCUGAAAGUAAGAAAGAGUGGACCAGCUUGCCUUAUCAAAUGAGCUGAAUCAUUUUACUGUGCUUAAUAGAUGUAAUUUCAUAUUGGGUAUCAGUCAAGAGUAAUGACUAACUCAAACAAAAUUAUAUAAGGUCAAAUUGACCUUUGAAAAAUGUUUCUAGAAAUUCUCUUUUGACUAUGUUUGGAGAAAGAAUUAAGUUAGAUGGACUUUCUAGUUGUGCCUAAGUCACAGUAUAUUGUGUAAAUGAAAGCUUCAGGUUUUGCAGAGCUACAUGCCCAUUUGAGUAUUCAUAUUUGUAAAUCAUCCUUCAGUAUGGAAUAGUUCUGUGAGGUAUGUUCAUAUUAACACAUGCUCAACACAAAAGACAAUCACCAUGCUUUUUACAUUUAAUAUUUUGCACGAUUCUGAUUAAGAAAGAACUUUAGAAAGUUUGGAGGAAAAUAAAUCCAGCUAGAAUGAUCUAGGGAUUAGAGUAGAAGAUUUGACUGAAAUAUUAAAGACCUCUUCACUCUGCAACUACAUAAGUUCAGUGAGAAGGUGUUUGAAGAAGAAACUUUAUGAUUCAGCCUUUCUCUUCGUUUCCUGGCUUGCAGGAAAUACAGCAUUGUACAUGGUAGGCAGUACAGAGAUUGCUGCCUGAAGAAGGUGGUGUACAGGAUUGGGGUGGAGGGAAGAGGAGGAAAUUUAUUUUCUGGAAAAGAUUUUGACCUACUGGAGAAAAAAAAGAAUUUAUGUUAAGAAAGGAAGUAGAUUACCCUUUUUAGAAAAAGUUUGUCAUAUAGUUGCAUUUUAGUUAGGAAUGUGUAACAUUUACUGUAUUUUAAAUUCUUUGUUCCAACAAGUUUUUUCCCCCAAUGUUGUCGGGGUUUUUUUGUUCUGAUUUGUCCUUUUUUUUUUUUUUUUUUUUUGAGACAGAAUCUCCCUCUGUCACCCAGGCUGGGGUACAGUGGCACGAUCAUGGCUCACUACAGCCUUGGCCUCCUGGGCUCAAGUGAUCCUCCUACAUCAGCCUCCCAAGUAGCUGGACUUCUAAAAUUUUUUGUAGAGAAAGGGUCCUCCUUUGUUGCCCAGGCUCAAUUGCUUUGUUUUGUUUUGUUUUGUUUUGUUUUGUUUUUGAGACAGAGUCCUCCCUCUGUCGUCAAGGCUAGAGUGCAGUGGUGCGAUCUCUGCUCACUGCAACCUCCGUCUACCGGGUUCAAGCGAUUCCCCUGCCUUAGCCUCCUGAGUAGCUGGGACUACAGGUGCCCGCCACCACGCCAGCUAAUUUUUUGUAUUUUUAUUAGAGAUGGGGCUUCACCAUGUUAGCCAGGAUGGUCUCGAUCUCCUGACCUCGUGAUCUGCCCACCUCGGUCUCCCAAAGUGCUGGGGUUACAGGUGUGAGCCACUGCGCCUGGCCUCAAUUGUUGUAUUGUGAUAAAAUACACAUAACACAGUUUAUCAUCUUAACCAUUUUAAAGUAUAUAGUUCAGUGGUAUUAAAUUCAGUGUUGUGCAGCCACCACCACCACCCAUCUGAAUAACUCUUUUUCUUUUUCUCUGAAAACUGCAACUAUAUCCAUUAAACAAGAACUCCUCAUUUCCCUCUCUCCUGAUUGCCUGGCAACUAUCAUUCUCAUUUCUAUUUCUGUGAUAUUAAUGUAAAAACCUUUUGUUACAUUCAUAAAUUACAAAUCUAUAGAAUACCAUAAAGGGAAAUGUGUUUUGGAAAAUCAUCUCAGACUUUUUUGAUUGCAAACUCUUAUUGUUAAAGAAGUUUAAAUGUUCCCCCAUAAACAUACUACUACAAUACUAAUAUGUAAAUUAAAAAAUUUAGAAGGUUGUAAUGAAGACAAUAUAUUUUUAAGUAUUUUGCUAAUUAUAAUAGUGCCAUGAUCAACAACUGAUAUCUCAAGACACAAAAAUAUAUUUAGGGCAAUAGUGGAUGUCAUUGAUUUUUCAAAUAAUCUUGAUAAUUUUUAAUGGGGAGGAGUGACAUUACCAGAUCUGAUUAAAUUAUAAUUUUCAAUUCCUAAUGAAGCUGGCAAAGGAGUAGAAGUGUCAGUGCUUAUUAUUUUCUUUUGUUGGUUUGUGCUUCCAUUACUGGUAUUAUAUUCAACCUAUGGUUUCUUGGGAGGAGUGUUUUUAAGCUGCUUAUUCAUUUGUGGUAGUUACACUGGUUAGAACUAAAUAACAUAAUAAAUAUUUAAUAAUAUAAUACAUGAAUCAUAUACUGCAUCACAUUAUUCUUAAAGUGAACAAGCCCAUGUACAAAUUAGGGGCCCUGUCUUCCUGUAUGCUGUAGAAUUCUCCCUGUUCUCUUCGGGUAUCUCCUAUGGACUGUGUGCAGCCAUCUGUGAUAAAGGCUGAAUGUGUGAGAGCAUUAGUGUCAAUCCAUUUAUAAAUUGUUGGUAACUUCAUUUGUUAGAUUAAAAACAUGAAAGUGAAUUAUGUCUUCCUCCUACAUCCCGAUGUGCUGUCUUGCACACUACUUAGAAUGUACACACCCUCCUCUGGAGAAACUUAGUUUAGGAUGUAUCUUGUAACCCUUUGAGAUUGUCUCCCCCUCCAAUAGCUUUACUGAGAUACUAAUUGACAAGUAAAAAAUGUAGUUUUAAGCUGUACAACAUGAUGUUUUGAUAUAUGUAUACACCAUGAGAUGAUUACCACAAUCAAGCUAAUUAGCAUAUGCAAGGUAAUAUCCAGUAACCUUGUGUGUGUUGAGAAUAUUUAAGAUCUACUUUCUUAGCAAAUUUCAAGUUUGCAAUAUAGUAUUAUUAACUAUAGUCAUUCUAACAUGUGAGGUGUUAUCUCAUUGUGGUUUUGAUUUGCAUUUUCCUGAUUAUUAGUGAUGUUGAUAAUUUUUUCAUAUACCUGUUGGCCAUGUGUAUGUCUUUUUUUGAGAAAUAUCCAUUGAAGUCCUUUACCUUUUUUUUUUUUUUUUUUUUUGAGACAGAGUCUCACUCUGUUGCCCAGGCUGGAGUGCAGUGGCUCACUACAACCUCCCCAUCCUGGGUUCGAGCACUUCUUUUGCCUCAGCCUCCUGAGUAGCUGGGACUACAGGCACAUGCUGCCAUGCCUGGCUAAUUUUUGUAUUUUUAGUAGAGAUGUGGUUUCACUGUGUUAGCCAGGCUAGUCUUGAACUCCUGACCUCAGGUGAUCCGCCCUCCUCAGCCUCCCAAAGUGCUGGGAUUACAGACAUGAGCCACCAUGCUCAGCCCCUUUACCCAUGUUUUAAUCAGGUUAUUUUCUUGCUAUUGAGUUGCUUGGAUUCCUUGUAUAUUUUGGAUAUAACUCCUUAUCAGGUCUAUGGUUUGAAAAUACAUUCUCCCAUUCUGUAGGUUGUCUCUUCACUUUGUUGAUUGUUUCUUUUGCUGUGCAGAAGUGAGGUUGCCUUUAUAUCUAUGUAUAGUGAUACAAAGUGAGGUUUCUAAUAUCUGUGUAUACUUGUAUUAUCCUGAAAGCAAAAAUGAAGUUUCCAGAUCAGAACCUGUCUAUUAUUACUUCACGACAGCAAAGGGUAUGGAGAAUGAGUAUUAUGAAUCUCCAUUGUAUUCUUUCUUCAUCUUGUUGCUGGACCUUACAGUUUUAAAUUUAGAAAGUUUAUUGUUCCAGUGAGACUGUAUAGUGCAGUAAGACAUUUAAGUACCAAAUACAACUAACUGAAAACCUUAAUCAGAAAUAUAUGCUAUAAUUCAACUUUGAAGAAAAAAAAUCAGAAGAAAACUAAAAGAGGUAAGCAGUUCUUUUCAUAAAAUCUUCCAGACUGUAUUUUGGGGUUUGUACACUUCCUUUUCAUGCAUACUUUGUCCUUUCAGCAGAUGGAUUGAGUACCUGUCACAACAAAAUCUGUGCCAGACACAUUCACAUUCAGCUUCUCAUUUCAUUCUCAAAAAAAGAAAAAAAAAACCCUUACAAAGAGGAUUAUUAUCCCCAUACCAUAAGAAAGGAUGUAGGCUCAGAGAAAUUAAGUAAUUUGCCUGUAGUAGAAUUCAAGCCAGAUUGCCUGUCUAAGAAAUAGUGUUCUUAAAUGAAGACCUGAAAUAUGUAAUUAUAUUAGUUCACUUCCUACUCUCAAAAUCUUUUCUGACCAUACUAAUUAUUACUCUUAACUUGAAAAAAAAUUGUUUCUAAUGGUAUGUCCACAACCUUCCUUGUUACCAUUUAGAUAUUUCAUGCAACUCUGUGACUUCAGUGUUAUAUUCUUGGUGGAUGAUUCACCAAGUCAGACAGAUUUGCUUCCUGAAUUCCAUAUCUAAGUAUCUCUGAGUCAAUGGCAGUACAUUUAGCCUCUCUGAGUCUGUGUCUUCAUUCAUAAAUUGUAGCUAGUAAUAUCCAUCUUACAAAAUUUGGAUGAGGAUUAAAUGAGAUAAUGUACCUGACACAUAGUAGGUUCUCAAGAAUGAUAGGUGCUUUCUUUCCAGCCCCCUAAACUCUAGUCUUCACCAAACUAGACAAACAAAGUAUCAAAUUACUGUUGAAAUUUAACAUAAUAAUUUCUUUCUUUGGUUUGGUUUUCUUGUUUUGUUUUGUUUUGUUUUGUUUGAGACAGGGUCUCACUUUGUCAUACAGGCUGGAGUGCAGUGGCGUGAUCUCAGCUCACUGCAGCCUCUCUACCUCCCAGGUUCAAGUGAUCCUCCUGCCUCAGCCCCCCCAAGUAACUGGAACUAUGGGCAUGCACCCCCACACCUGGCUAAUUUUUCUAUUUUUUUGCAGAGGCAGGAUUUGGCCAUGUUGCCCAAGCUGGUCUUGAACUCCUGAGCUCAAGUCAUCCACCUGCCUCAGCCUCCCAAAGUGCUAGGAUUACAGACAUGAGCCACUAUGCCCAGCCCCUAGUAAUUUCUCUCCCUCCCUAAUCAGCAGCUCGUUUUAGUUUCCAAAUUUCUAUUAAAUCCUCCCAAUUACACAAGUUUAAAGUCUAUUUAACAUUCAUUUUGGCAACUUCUUACUUGCCUACUACAUCUACGUAGUUGUUAAGCCUUAAAGAGUCUAGCUCUUUACGGCCACCCUUUCUAGCUCCCACCCUAGUUUAGACCAUCAUUACUAUUAUUCCAAAUUUUAUAGCAGCUUCAUAAAUGGUCUCCCCUCUUUGCUCACUCACUUCCCUUCUAUCCUGCAUAUUAUAAUCCCCGUUAGUCUUUUUUUUUUUUUUUAACAAGAAGUUUAUUUAAACAACAAGACACUUGACUUGAAGGGAAAACUAUCUAAGAUUCUUUUUUGUUUUAGGGUAAUUUAUCCCUACUUAAAGACAGAUUGCCCUACAUAUAACAGCUACAUACAAAAAAGUUAUAAAACUGUCCUUGGUUUUACAAUGAUAAAUGAAAAACAUUAAAAUUCUCCAACUGAAAAAGGUAUGCAAGGAUUUUUGUUGUUGUUAAAACAGAGCAAAAUAACUUACUGGAAUAUAAAGAUAAGAGCUGAAUGAGCAUGCCGCUAAUGGAGAAAGGGGGUAUUUUCACAGAAUCAGUAUUUUUCCCCAUCCCGUCUCCACUUGAUGUCAAUCAAAACAUACCAUUGGCUGUUUAGUUGAAAAAAAAAUGCAAUAUGCUUGUGCACAUACACCAGUUACUUUAUGUACAAUAAAGGAAUGGGGAAGGGGAAAAUGAAAGAAUAGAGAAAACUAUACAGUUUUAGUCAGGAUGUGGUGGAACCAAAUUGCAGUUUUCUAAUUGAGAAUGUAAUCUUGGUCUUUAAAGAACAGAGUUCUGGCGUAAAGAAGCAGGUUCUGAGAUUUCUCAUGUAUUUUUCCAGAGCCAGACUUACAGAAUGCACUUUUGAAGGGGGAGUAUAAACGUUUGCUUAUUUAUUCAAUUUUGUUUAAAAUAAUUGGAUAACAUUUUAUGUACCUACAGUGCUCUCAGCAUGCUGGGAAUGAACUAUCAUUUUGGAGGUGGGGUAAUAUUUUUGUUUUUGUUCUUUGUUAAUUUUUUUCCCCUUAGGAUAAAAGCUCACUGGUUGUGGCCGGGCGCAGUGGCUCAUGCCUGUAAUCCCAGCACUUUGGGAGGCCAAGGCGGGCAGAUUUUGAGGUCAGGAGAUCGAGACCAUCCUGGCCAACAUGGUGAAACCCCAUCUCUACUAAAAAUACAAAAAUUAGCUGGGCAUGGUGGCACAUGCCUGUAGUCCCAGCCACUCGGGAAGCUGAGGCAGGAGAAUCGCUUGGAUCCAGGAGCGGAGGUUGCAGUGAGACAAGAUCGUGCCAAGACUCUGUCUCAAAAAAAAAAAAAAAAAAAAAAAAAAAAAAAAGCUCACUGGUUCUAUUUCAGAGCUCACAAUUGAUUAAUAGCACUAAAAGAAAAUCAUUUCCCCAAUUAUGUCCCAAAAUAUCUAAAGAAUUACCCAUCUGAAUUGUCCUUAUUUUUUUCUCUUCUCUAAAACUACUCCUUUUAUCAUACAAAAUAUGUACCUGGAAAUUUAAGUUAUAUUUUAAGAAUGGUAUUUCUUUCAAAUACUUAUAUAACUUUAUUAAUAGGCUAAAAUGUGGUUCAAUACAAAAUUAUGUGACUCAUGGAAAGGGUCUUAUCUAGUUUAAUAUUCUGAUGUGGCCUCUUUUCUCAUCCCUUUUGUAUCAAAAAGAUAUUCAAUUAUAGUUUGACUUAUGUAAAAUCCCAGGUUCAUAAUAGAUAUUUCAAUCCAAAUCCAUUUUGUGUUGUGAUCUGGAUGACAGAAGAAGCUCAGCCUUCCUCAAAAGGGAAUAAAAAUUUGAAUCCAGGUUCUAAGUCUACUGCAGCUUAGUGUGUUUAGUAGAACCUAAAGCAGUUGUGGUGAGUCAUGAGUCUUCCUCCGUGAUUGGCCUGAUGUCUCAACAUCCCCUGUAGUCUUUUCCUUUGACUGCUGUAACAAAUUACCAAAAACUGGAUGGCUUAAAACAACAGAAAUAUAUUCUCUCACAGUUUUGAAGGCCAGAAAGUCUGAAUUCAGUACCUCUGAGCCAAAAUCCAGGCAUGGGUAGGGCCAUGCCACCUCUGGACACCCUAUGGAAGGACUUGUUCCCUUCCUCUUCCAGCUUCUGUUGGCUGCUGGCAUUCCUUGGCUUGUGGCCACAUCAUACCAGCCCUCAAGGCCAGCAUUGUCAAAUCUCUCUCUGCUCUGUGCUCACAUUGCCUUCCCCUCUGUGUGCCUGUGAAAUCUCCCCCUGCCUCUCUUAAAGACAAGCAAUCAAAUUGAUUGCUUUGAGGGCAUACCCUGAUAAAUCAGGAUAGUCUCAUCUCAAGAGCCUUAACUUAAUCACAUAUACAAAGACCUUUCUUCCAAAUAAGGUAACAUUUACAAGCAUUAGGGCUUGAUGUCUUUGGGGUGGGCAUUUUCACCCUACCAUAUCUUCUAAGGUCUCAUACUACUUUGGGCCAUAUAGAUCUUAGGAAGCCCAAAUUCUCAGAUAGAAUUUAAGGUUUCAAUCUGCACUGCCAGCUUUGCUGCAACCCAGGAUCAUCUCAGAAUCCUUUCACAGAAUUCUUAUUCAUAAGUAUGUCUUAACCCUAAACUCCUAAGAAAACACAUCUAGAUUUAUACUAAGUAACAUGCUAGGAACUCAGUCUUGAAAACUCAAUCUCUCUUAUAACCUCCACUUCCAAUGUAUAAAUUGAGAAGAGUAUGGUCUAUACAUUGGGUUGUGAAAAUUAACAAUGAGUAGUGACAAAGCAGAGGCCCUGACACAUAGUAUGUAUUCAAUAAAUACCAUGCUUAUUAUCCUACAUCAGAAGGGCAAGCCAUCCUUAAAGUUUGAUAGUAAGCCAGAAAUCUAAAUAAUUAGUUAAAAGGAACAAAGGGAGAGGAGAGAAAUCCCAAGGUGCUCUUCAUGGAUGACUAAUGGGAGAUAUCUCCUAUGACGUAUGGGCCUUUAGGCUCUUAAAUAGCUUCAGGGCAGGAUGCACCAAAUAGGGCCCGAAGUUUCCAUAUCCCUGGAGGGGAAAAACAAAUAAAUAAAUAAAUAAGAACUGCUUUGCUUCUGAAUGGAGGGGAGAAAGCUGUACUAAUAAUAAUUAUUCUGGAUGGUUCUAAUGUCCUUUAACUCCUUUAGCAGGCCUAUGUUGUGAUUUGAGGACUACCAUAUUGAAUAUGAAUUAUUUCUUAUUGACUGGGCUUCCCCAUCUGAGUUAUCUCAGGACUUGGACAAAACAGCUCUGCCCCACCCCCUCAAAUCCAGAACAAUUCAAAUAGAAAAGUGUGUGUGGUCAUGAAUACGCCACAGUUUCCCCAGUCUCUAUUGGUUUGUGUGCAAGAGAUAGAUCAAAUAUUAAUUUACACUUUACUGGUCUAUUGACUAUUCAAGUAAAAUUGACAAAUACUGGUCAACUACAAUUAUCUCUCCCCUCCUUAUUAAAAUAUGACAUUAUGUAAAUCUCUGGUGAAUGAUACAAAAUAGAAAUGUAACAAGGCUGAAAUAUCGUAAGAAUCUAAGUUCAAAUUUUACCUACAGAAUUUUUAAUUCCAUAAACAUUUGUGAUAUAACUACACUGUGCCAGGCAUUAUACCAACCUCUGAAGACAAGACCAAGCUCUGAAGAAUCAAUGAUAAAAAAGACAUGGUGCCUCCUUCAAGAGAGCACCUUGUGAACCAUGAGCCAAGUGGAAACAAAUGCAGUCAUCCUGAUUGUCUUAGUUUGGGCUGCUGUAACAAAGUACCAUAGACUGGGUGGCUUGUGAACAACAGACAUUCAUUUCUCACAGUUCUGGAGACUGGAAAUCUAAGAUCAGGGUGCCAGCACAGAUUGGGUUCUGGCGAAGCCAUCCUCUGGAUUGCAGACUGUCAUCUUCUCCCUGUAUCCUUACGUGGCAGAAAAAGGGCAGGAGAGUUCUUUGAGGUCUCUUUUAGAAGGGCACCAAUCCCAUUCAUUAGGGCUCUAUUCUGAUGAACCAAUCACCUCCGAGAGGCUCCACCUCCUGAUAGCAUCACAUUUAGGGUUAGGUUUUCAAGAUAUGAAUUUGGGGUCAGGGGGACACAAUCAUUCAGUCAAUUACAUUAAUUUCACCUGGCAAGAACGGUUGAAAUGACGCAGUGGUAUCUUUUUCUCAAAAGAAGUGAUAUUUGAUCUGAGCUUUGAAGAAGCAAACAGAGAGAAAUUAUGAGGGCAUACAAGGGUUGGAGAAGGUAUUCCAGACAGAAGCAACAGCAAUUUCAAUGGCACUCAGGCAUAAGUGCAAUGGUGGUCACUGGAGGUCAAGUGGAUGGAAUGGUAGGACUGGAUCAUAUUGAGAGCCUUUACAUCACAAUCAAGAGUUUAGACUCUAUUUUAUGGGCAUCCAGAUACCAUGAGAAGGAGAUGUGAUGCAUGUGAGCUUUACCUCAGCUGUGAGACCUUGUCUGCCCUCAGGCUCUCUGCUACAAAAGCAGCCUGCCUGCCAAAGACCUGUUUGCAAAACUCUUCACUCCACCAUGACCAGAGCACCUCUCCUGCUACUAUGUGUUGCCCUGGUGCUGCUUGGGCAUGUGAAUGGAGCCACAGUAAGAAAUGAGGACAAAUGGAAGCCACUCAACAACCCCAGAAACAGAGAUCUGUUUUUCAGAAGGCUUCAGGCAUAUUUUAAGGGCAGAGGUCUUGAUCUUGGAACAUUUCCAAAUCCUUUCCCCACGAAUGAAAAUCCUAGACCUCUCUCUUUCCAGUCAGAACUUACUGCUUCUGCAUCUGCAGAUUAUGAAGAGCAGAAAAACUCCUUUCACAAUUAUCUCAAAGGCUGAAAGUUUCUUCUGAGCUCAGGUGUCUGGCUAUUUUAAAACUACAGAUGAAGCUUCUCAUUAGAAAAAUUCAACCAUUGUCAUAGCUAAACUUUCAUGGAGUUUCUUUCCCCCUCACUUUUAUUUUUCAGUUUGUAAUGAUUUUAUUCCACAUUUCCAUAUUUACAUAUAAAUCGCUGGAACUAUGAUUUCUAUGCAUAUUUAUGGAGUUUUUUUCCUAUGAAACCAUAAAUAUUGAUGUAGAGCACCGCAUGUAUUUGUAGGAGUUACAAAAACAUCACAAACUGAAAAAAGAUUAUAAUCUAAAUUAGAUGUUUCUUUAAGCUUGUUUUUAAAACUUGUCUUUUAUGUUUAUUAUCUUUUAUCGACCAAUAUAUUUUUUUAAAGGGACAUGCUCACUUUUAGUAUAGUAAAAUUCAUUAUAUGUGAUAGAGGGUUGGGUUUAAAAUUUGUCUUCCUUUCCUAAAAAGAAGAUGCAUUCCCAUGUUCAGCAUACACUACCAAAAUACUUCACAGUUUUAGUUUCAUAAGAAAUGAGGGCAAGUGAUAAACAGCCACAAUUAAGUUAAAAUGGAAGCAAACAACAACAACAAACAUGGGAUUCUAGAAGUUGUCAACGCCUCCAAAGAUGCUCUUUGCCAGAGUAUUCAGAGGUGGACAUUGUGCCACAUCAAAUAUUCUAGCAAUGCCCGAGCCCUUGCUCUCAUACACAACCUCCUCAGGAAGGAAAAGUAGAAACAGGUGAUUUCCUCUCUUUCCAACCAGCCCCUGCUCUCCUUACUCUAGCUCAUGCUGAGUUAUUCUGAUUCCCAUACUCACAUUUGGAAUAGCUGCUUUUCCUGUAUCUUUAUAGAUAGCUGCAUCAUCUUCUCUGUGAUUCCUGCAAAAGGAAUGUUGCACUAAAAUGCAACAUUGUCCUAACAUUAGUCUGUGCAUUUCAAAAUAUUUUAAUGUGGCUUUUUUGGGUGGAUUAUUGAUAUUGUAUAUGAAGAAUAAAAUAUUUGUGCAAGAACA